AACGCAGAGUUGGGAGCAACUCCAGAGCCUCCUUCAAGAUGCUGCUGGUCCUGCUCUCAGUGGUCCUUCUGGCUCUGAGCUCAGCUCAGAGCACAGAUAAUGAUGUGAACUAUGAAGACUUUACUUUCACCAUACCAGAUGUAGAGGACUCAAGUCAGAGACCAGAUCAGGGACCCCAGAGACCUCCUCCUGAAGGACUCCUACCUAGACCCCCUGGUGAUAGUGGUAACCAAGAUGAUGGUCCUCAGCAGAGACCACCAAAACCAGGAGGCCAUCACCGCCAUCCUCCCCCACCUCCUUUUCAAAAUCAGCAACGACCACCCCGACGAGGACACCGUCAACUCUCUCUACCCCGAUUUCCUUCUGUCAGCCUGCAGGAAGCAUCAUCAUUCUUCCAGAGGGACAGACCAGCAAGACAUCCCCAGGAGCAACCACUCUGGUAAUCUAGAAUUCAGUGGCAGAAAAUAAAUAAGAAGAUAACUUCCUUCAGAAAGCCAUGACAUUGAAAUAAUGUGGUCAUAACUCUUUCUUCAGUAUACCAAUAAAAUAUUAAUAGCAUGCAA